ACUUUCCUGCGCAGGGGGAUCGGGGCGCACUCGCCGGUGCCGCGGUUCCCAGGUCGAGGGCAGUGGGGUAGGGGGCGCCGCGCUUUUUCUCGCGGGCGCCGUGGUUCCCGUGCGGCCUUGGACGCGAGUCUCCCCCUGCAGGCCUGGUCCCUGGUCCUGGUCACCCGUGCAACUGGAGCGGCGCUCCGCGUUUGGAAAGGGUUUUGAAGGGGGUUCUAAGGGGGAGUGGGCGCCUAGGACUCCCUAUGGGAGUCGGUGGGUUAUACCUUGACUGCCGUUGAUUUUUAUUUAACUGUUUAGCUUAGUGACUCAAGUGUUCCCCUUUUCUUGGGGAUGAGUAAACUGAGGCUCAUUAAAGAGCUUGUGACCAAACAACACAGGUGCCCCAGAGAAAGGUCGGGCCUGGAAACUACAAAGGAUUGUGUUAAUUUUGUGUUUAGGAAGAAAGAGGUAAUGGGUAGGAAUCAAUGUAAACUUAUUCAUAGGCCACACCAAACCAGGAAUUCUUGUCGUGAUUGCACUUGGUAGAGUUAACACACGUGCACAUUACGGAAACGUUGGUGACCAACAGGCGUUUCAGCGAGCUUUCGCACACCUCAUGGGCCUUUGUGGGCUGCUGGAGAGAUGUUGGCUGCACCAUGACCCAGAUGGAGUUUUAACAUUGAAUGCGGAGAACACUAAUUAUGCCUAUCAAGUUCCAAACUUCCAUAAAUGUGAAAUCUGUCUACUAUCUUUUCCAAAAGAAUCCCAGUUUCAACGCCACAUGAGGGAUCACGAGCGAAAUGACAAGCCACAUCGAUGUGACCAGUGCCCCCAAACAUUUAAUGUUGAAUUCAACCUGACACUUCAUAAAUGCACCCACAGCGGGGAAGAUCCUACCUGCCCUGUGUGUAACAAGAAAUUCUCCAGAGUGGCUAGUCUCAAAGCGCAUAUUAUGCUACAUGAAAAGGAAGAGAAUCUCAUCUGUUCUGAGUGUGGGGAUGAGUUUACUCUGCAGAGUCAGCUGGCCGUGCACAUGGAGGAGCACCGCCAGGAGCUGGCUGGAACCCGGCAGCAUGCCUGCAAGGCCUGCAAGAAAGAGUUCGAGACCUCCUCGGAGCUGAAGGAACACAUGAAGACUCAUUACAAAAUUAGGGUAUCAAGUACAAGGUCUUAUAACCGGAAUAUCGACAGAAGUGGAUUCACGUAUUCGUGUCCGCACUGUGGAAAGACGUUUCAAAAGCCAAGCCAGUUAACGCGACACAUUAGGAUACACACAGGUGAAAGGCCGUUCAAAUGUAGUGAAUGUGGAAAGGCUUUUAACCAGAAGGGGGCACUGCAGACCCACAUGAUCAAGCACACAGGUGAAAAACCCCAUGCCUGUGCCUUCUGUCCUGCCGCCUUCUCUCAGAAAGGGAAUCUUCAGUCGCACGUGCAGCGAGUCCACUCAGAGGUCAAGAAUGGUCCUACCUAUAACUGUACAGAAUGUAGUUGUGUAUUUAAAAGUUUAGGCAGCUUAAACACGCAUAUCAGCAAGAUGCAUAUGGGUGGGCCACAGAAUUCAACAAGUUCUACAGAGACUGCUCAUGUUUUAACGGCCACACUUUUUCAGACGUUACCUCUUCAACAGACGGAAGCCCAAGCCACGUCGGCCUCAAGCCAGCCGAGCUCCCAGGCGGUGAGCGACGUCAUCCAGCAGCUCCUGGAGCUCUCAGAGCCGGCGCCGGUGGAGUCGGGGCAGUCCCCGCAGCCUGGGCAGCAGCUGAGCAUCACAGUGGGCAUCAACCAGGACAUUUUACAGCAAGCCUUAGAAAACAGUGGGCUGUCUUCAAUUCCAGCUGCAGCACAUCCUAAUGACUCCUGCCAUGCCAAGACCUCUGCACCACACGCUCAAAACCCAGAUGUUUCCAGCGUUUCAAAUGAGCAGACGGACCCCACAGACGCAGAGCAAGAAAAAGAACAGGAAAGCCCGGAGAAACUGGAUAAAAAAGAAAAAAAAAUGAUAAAGAAGAAGUCACCGUUUCUACCUGGCUCCAUCCGCGAGGAGAACGGCGUGCGCUGGCAUGUGUGUCCCUACUGCGCCAAGGAGUUCCGCAAGCCCAGCGACCUGGUCCGCCACAUCCGCAUCCACACCCACGAGAAGCCCUUCAAGUGCCCGCAGUGCUUCCGCGCCUUCGCCGUGAAGAGCACGCUGACAGCGCACAUCAAGACGCACACCGGCAUCAAGGCGUUCAAGUGCCAGUACUGCAUGAAGAGCUUCUCCACCUCUGGCAGCCUCAAGGUGCACAUUCGCCUGCACACAGGAGUUAGACCUUUUGCUUGUCCUCACUGUGACAAAAAAUUUCGAACCUCAGGCCAUAGGAAGACUCACAUUGCUUCCCACUUUAAACAUACGGAAUUAAGGAAAAUGAGGCACCAGCGUAAACCUGCAAAGGUCCGUGUUGGCAAGACGAAUAUUCCAGUCCCUGAUAUUCCUUUGCAGGAACCAAUCCUCAUAACUGACUUAGGUCUCAUCCAGCCCAUUCCAAAAAACCAGUUUUUCCAAAGCUAUUUCAAUAAUAAUUUUGUCAAUGAAGCAGAUAGACCAUACAAGUGUUUUUACUGUCAUCGUGCAUAUAAAAAAUCUUGCCACCUUAAACAACACAUCAGAUCCCAUACAGGUGAAAAACCUUUUAAAUGUUCUCAGUGUGGAAGAGGCUUUGUUUCUGCAGGCGUGCUCAAAGCACACAUCAGAACACACACAGGACUGAAAUCUUUCAAGUGUCUGAUAUGUAAUGGGGCUUUCACUACUGGUGGCAGCUUACGGCGACACAUGGGUAUCCACAACGACCUUCGUCCCUAUAUGUGUCCCUAUUGCCAAAAAACAUUUAAGACUUCACUAAAUUGCAAAAAGCACAUGAAAACCCACAGAUAUGAGCUUGCCCAGCAGCUCCAACAGCAUCAGCAGGCAGCCUCGAUAGAUGACAGCACUGUAGACCAGCAGAGCAUGCAGGCCUCCACUCAAAUGCAGGUGGAGAUCGAGAGCGACGAGCUGCCGCAGACGGCAGAGGUGGUCGCAGCGAACCCCGAGGCCAUGCUGGACCUGGAGCCUCAGCAUGUGGUGGGCACGGAGGAAGCAGGGCUGGGCCAGCAGUUGGCAGAUCAGCCCCUGGAAGCAGAUGAAGAUGGGUUUGUGGCUCCACAGGACCCUCUGCGAGGGCACGUAGACCAGUUUGAAGAGCAGAGCCCUGCGCAACAGUCCUUCGAACCAGCAGGGCUACCCCAAGGUUUUACAGUGACUGAUACGUACCAUCAGCAGCCUCAGUUUCCACCUGUCCAACAGCUACAGGAUUCCAGCACACUUGAGUCUCAGGCCCUCUCCACAAGCUUCCACCAGCAGAGCUUGCUGCAGGCUCCCAGCUCUGAUGGGAUGAAUGUAACAACUCGCUUGAUUCAGGAGUCAUCCCAAGAGGAACUGGACCUGCAGGCACAAGGUUCCCAGUUUCUGGAGGACAACGAGGACCAGAGCAGGCGCUCUUACAGGUGUGACUAUUGCAACAAAGGCUUUAAGAAGUCCAGCCACCUGAAGCAGCAUGUGCGGUCGCACACCGGGGAAAAGCCCUACAAGUGCAAGCUCUGUGGACGCGGCUUUGUUUCCUCUGGGGUCCUCAAGUCCCACGAGAAGACACACACAGGAGUGAAGGCGUUCAGCUGCAGUGUGUGCAAUGCUUCCUUCACCACCAAUGGCAGCCUCACCCGGCACAUGGCCACACAUAUGAGCAUGAAGCCUUAUAAGUGUCCGUUUUGUGAGGAGGGUUUCCGAACUACAGUGCAUUGUAAAAAGCACAUGAAGAGACACCAAACAGUCCCCUCUGCUGUGUCAGCCACUGGAGAGACAGAAGGAGGAGACAUUUGUAUGGAGGAAGAGGAAGAACAUUCUGACAGAAAUGCAUCACGGAAGUCUCGUCCUGAGGUCAUCACUUUCACGGAGGAGGAGACAGCCCAGUUAGCCAAGAUCCGGCCGCAGGAGAGCGCCACGGUGUCAGAGAAGGUCCUGGUGCAGUCCGCGGCAGAAAAGGACCGCAUCAGUGAGCUGAGGGACAAGCAGGCGGAGCUGCAGGACGAGCCCAAGCACGCCAACUGCUGCACAUACUGCCCCAAGAGCUUCAAGAAACCUAGCGACCUGGUGAGGCAUGUUCGAAUCCAUACUGGAGAAAAGCCAUACAAAUGUGAUGAAUGUGGAAAGAGUUUUACUGUGAAAUCCACUCUCGAUUGUCAUGUGAAGACUCACACAGGUCAGAAGCUCUUCAGCUGUCACGUCUGCAGCAACGCCUUCUCCACGAAGGGAAGUCUGAAGGUCCACAUGCGCCUGCACACGGGAGCCAAGCCCUUCAAAUGCCCGCAUUGCGAGCUGCGUUUCCGUACCUCGGGUAGAAGAAAGACACACAUGCAGUUUCAUUAUAAACCAGACCCAAAGAAGGCCAGAAAGCCUAUGACUCGAAGCUCAUCGGAAGGACUGCAGCCUGUAAACCUCCUCAACUCCUCCUCUACUGACCCAAACGUGUUUAUCAUGAACAACUCUGUUCUAACAGGACAGUUUGAUCAGAAUCUGCUGCAACCAGGACUGGUGGGCCAAGCUAUUCUCCCUGCCUCUGUGUCAGCUGGGGGUGACCUGACCGUGUCUCUGACAGAUGGGAGCCUGGCUACCCUAGAAGGCAUCCAGUUACAGUUGGCUGCUAACUUGGUUGGACCAAAUGUACAGAUUUCUGGAAUCGAUGCUGCCAGCAUUAAUAACAUUACGUUGCAGAUUGAUCCAAGCAUUCUGCAGCAGACGCUACAGCAGGGCAACCUAUUGGCUCAGCAGCUCACGGGGGAGCCUGGCCUGGCCCCACAGAACAGCUCUCUCCAGACAUCGGACAGCACGGUCCCUGCCAGUGUUGUCAUCCAGCCCAUCUCAGGCCUGUCCUUACAGCCCACAGUGACCUCUGCGAACCUGACCAUAGGCCCGCUGUCUGAGCAGGAUUCAGUGCUGACCACUAACAGCAGUGGGACCCAAGACCUCACUCAAGUGAUGACUUCGCAAGGUCUAGUGUCCCCCUCCGGCGGUCCCCACGAGAUCACCCUGACCAUUAACAACUCCAGCCUGAGCCAGGUCCUGGCACAGGCCGCUGGGCCCACUGCCACGUCUUCCUCGGGGUCUCCACAGGAAAUUACCCUGACUAUCUCCGAACUUAACACUACAAGCGGAAGCCUUCCUUCAACAACACCGAUGUCUCCAUCGGCCAUCUCGACUCAGAACCUGGUCAUGUCCUCGUCGGGCGUGGGAGGUGACGCUAGUGUCACGCUGACGCUGGCCGAUACUCAGGGUAUGCUAUCUGGAGGCCUGGACACUGUCACACUCAACAUCACCUCUCAGGGUCAGCAGUUCCCAGCGCUCCUCACGGAUCCCUCUCUCUCGGGCCAGGGUGGAGCAGGCUCGCCGCAAGUCAUACUAGUGAGCCACACGCCACAGUCAGCGUCUGCUGCUUGUGAAGAAAUAGCCUACCAGGUAGCUGGCGUCUCUGGGAACCUGGCCCCGGGCAACCAGCCAGAGAAGGAGGGCCGGGCGCACCAGUGCCUGGAGUGUGACCGCGCCUUCUCAUCGGCGGCGGUGCUCAUGCACCACAGCAAGGAGGUGCAUGGCCGGGAGCGCAUCCACGGCUGCCCCGUGUGCAGGAAGGCCUUCAAGCGCGCCACGCACCUCAAGGAGCACAUGCAGACACACCAGGCCGGCCCCUCUUUGAGCUCCCAGAAGCCAAGAGUGUUUAAAUGUGACACUUGUGAGAAGGCAUUUGCCAAACCAAGCCAGCUGGAGCGCCACAGCCGCAUACAUACAGGGGAGCGGCCGUUCCAUUGCACGCUUUGUGAGAAAGCCUUCAACCAGAAGAGUGCGCUGCAGGUGCACAUGAAGAAGCACACGGGGGAGCGGCCCUACAAGUGUGCCUACUGCGUCAUGGGCUUCACGCAGAAGAGCAACAUGAAGCUGCACAUGAAGCGGGCGCACAGCUAUGCUGGAGCUCUGCAGGAGUCUGCAGGUCACCCGGAGCAGGACGGGGAGGAGCUGAGCCGGACCCUCCACCUGGAGGAGGUGGUGCAGGAGGCCGCCGGCGAGUGGCAGGCCCUCACCCACGUCUUCUGAUGCGAGUUGGAAGUACACCUUUAAGAAUGUUUCUGAAGUUACGUUUUGUGAAGAGCAAAGCACUUGGAAUCUCCGUUUUAAAGCUUCAAGUGUUAAAAAUGCUACAAUAGUUUUUUAUCUAUAAAAUUAUCUAAAGAAUCAUUGUCUUUCAGAGACUCAUAGGAAAAAAAAACUAGGAAAAGUGUCACCGCAUUGUUCUCUUUUGUCUACAAAUCACUGAACUCAGGUACUACUGUAGGCAGUUUCCUCCUCAGUCUCCUCCGUGGCUAGUGUGUCUAGUUCACGAAGCAAUUAACUGGGUCUUACUAUCAUUGUAGUGUGAUUUCUUUGUAUUAGCAAAGACAAAAACGCUAACAUUGAAAAAGUAUGUCAGAUUUUCCUUCAUGUUUCUGGUUAUAAGAAGCAUAGCUUACAAAGCAAGCGUAAGAUUGAGGCAUGAAGUUCAGAAAAAAAAGUGUUACAACACACAGGGAAGUUUUUUCCACUCUUUUCUCUGUGCAUUUUGAAAAUUAGUCAAAAUGGACUCUUUUCAGUCUACCAUAAGUUAAUAUAACUGAUACCUUGAGAGAUGGCUGGACCAAUUCUCUCCAUGACAAAUGUUUAAUCAUUAGUUACAAGAAUGCAGUAUCUGGGGCGUCAACAUGGGGACUCGAGUAAACCUGACCCACCAAUAAGGAUUCAGCUGUCCACACGGGCUGGCGACACACUUACCGCAUCAAUCUGUGUUCAGGUCCAGGGUUACAUAAUUGCAGAAGCACAAGCCAUACAUCGCAGGUAGGAAACCACAGAACCGUCUGCAAGGAGCAAGCAACGGUGGCCCUGUCCACCCCAGCAAAUAAGAAGCAUAUCUGUAGCUUAAGGCCACGAAUCCGUAAAAACCCCAUGACUUUCUCUUCGUGCAUAAACAGAUGUAUUUUUGAUUUCAGGGAAUUCUUUAGUAUCGUCAAUGGUGCCACAUAAAACAUGUCCCAAACCAAAUCCCACCCGUGCUGGGCAGAGUGCGUGCACGCCAUUCCUACAGCAUUCCAAAGAUGGAAGGUUCUUUACUUCAUGUUAAUUUUUCCUUUGAAAUUAUUUAUAUGUUCUAUAUAUAAAUACAUAUGUACAUAGAUAUAUGGGCCUCUGUGUGGCUGAACAGUAUAUUUUGUAAAUAUAAGUACUAGUCCUAAUUGCAGAAAGAGCGUCAGUUUCACCUCCCCACGAGCACUUCAGAUCAGUAUUGUAUUCAUUUUAUUCAUAAAUGGAUAUCUUUUUCAUUGUCAUAUAAAGCUGGGUUUUAUUUUUUUUUCCUGAAAAAUAAUUGCCUUUAUUUUCUCUCGUUGCCUCCUUGGUUUCAGAAGAGAGUAGUUUUAUUAUAAAUAUUGUAUGGACUUUGUAUAUUAAGAGAGGAGCUCAUUUCAGAUUCCUAAAGAAAUAGACAUUUUACUGUUAUUUUGAAAGGGCAUCUUUUGAUUUUUUUGUUGUUGUUGUUCACUUUUGGCAUAUGUAUAUAAGUAAUAUUGACGGUGAUAUGAAAACUUUUGUUAUGUGAAGAUAUUUAAGUCAGAAAAUUGUUAAAUAAUAUUACUUCUUUUCCAAACUGCUUUGUGUAUUGUAUAUUUUUUUAAGAAAAAGAAAAGCCUUAUUUGACUUAUGCUUGUGAUACUGGACUUCUUACCAAUCCGGAGGUUUCCUUCCUUGAAUGUCAGUGUGUAAACCUGGCUGUAGCCGCAUAUGCAGAAUAACUGUAAUUGUGCUAGAGUUUUAAAGGUUCUGCUUUUAAUGCACUUUUUAUUUUAUAAUUUUGUAUUGAAAUAUUUUAGAAAUGUUGAUUAAUUUUGGUGAAAAAAUAUCCCCAAAGUGGAAAUUAUUGGAAUUUUAAACUUUUGUUCUUGCUGGGUUAUUUAUUUUGAUUUUAGCAUUAAAUGUCAUCUCAGGACAUCUCUAAAAGGGGUUGUUUAAUUCCUAAUUGUAUAGAAAGCUAGUUUGGUGAAUUGUAUUGGUUAAUUGACUGUUUAAGGCCUUAACAGGUGAAUCUAGAGCCUACUUUUAUUUUGGUUAAAGAAAAAGAAAAUAUCAAUAAUUCAAUUUUGUGUCUUUUCUCAAUUUAUUAGCAAACACAAGACAUUUUAUGUAUUAUUUCGAUUUACUUCCUAAUUAUAAAAGCUGCUUUUUUGCAGAACAUUCCUUGAAAAUAUAAGGUUUUGAAAAGACAUAAUUUUACUUGAAUCUUUGUGGGGUACAGGUUGAUCUUUAUAUUUUACUGGUUGUUUUAAAAAUUCUAGAAAAGAGAUUUCUAGGCCUCAUGUAUAACCAGGGUUUUGAGGAUAAAGAACUGUAUUUUUAGAACUAUCUCAUCAUAGCAUAUCUGCUUUGGAAUAACUAUAAAUAAAAGAUGAAGUUAGGAAAUGUGAUUAAUUUUUUUCGUUUGAAAAUAUUUAAGAUAAAACAGUUUGGCAUGUAAAUUAAUUUCAAGUUCAGAUAUUUUUAAGAGAAAACUUUAGUGGUAUUUUCCUUUACCUCUGUGAAGUUCAGAGGCGUUUACCCCUGCAGUGUCCACUGGAAAGGCUUCAGACUUUCAAAAUCAGGGCAUGGCUCCGCGACAGCGAGCCGUGGGCGUCAGCACAGUGCCCUGUGCAUGUGUCAGAACUGUUCCUGUUCCCUUUCAUUUGCUGCUUUAUUCAACGGCACCCAGUCAUUGAGGAACCUUUUGAAAGUUCCUAAGUGUUUUGAUCCUGCUUGUGUGCUCAAGUAACCAUGAAGCACUGAAGCUGAAAGAAUGAAUUGCCUUUGCAAAGAUACCAAACGUGAAGGUGGGGUGCAGGUACUGAGGAAGCAGGAGGCAUGUAGCAUGUGUGGAGUCCCACCUGCUAGAUAAUGCCCAAGCGGCUGCGUUUCCAUAGAAUGGCAAUAGAUGAAAAUGAAGACAUGUUUUCAAACAUGCAGAUUGAAAUGCUACCCCACCCCCAUCAAGCUCUACUUUUUCCCCUUUGAAAAACUUGAGGCACUUAGAAAGUAUCUAAAUAGAGGAAAUGCUAUGACAUGGCAUCUGACAGCUUGCAGCCAGGUCAGUGGGAGGCUCAUCAAAUGCCACUCUCCUCUUCCUGACAGUGUUCUGCUGGUGGGACAUGAACAUCAGUGCUUGUCUGGCACUUAACUAGGGGAUGUUUCCUUCGUGCAUAUUUUCUACUCCCCUGUUGUAAUAUUUUAAGGAAACUUGAUCUUUGAAAUUAUAGCUAGUGUUCUGUGUCUUCCUUUGAACUCAUAUCACAUUUAUUACAAGAGACGCAUGUGUUAGCACAGCUACACAAUUUUUAGAAGUAGAAGUGGAUUUCUUGUCUUGCUGUGGGUUUUCCUCAUUUUAGAAGAAUAUUUGUAACUCAUUAAGAUACACAUUUUAACAUGAAAUGACCAUCACACAGAUUUAUGUUUGGAAAUAUUCAAGAUAAAAUAGUUUGGCAUGUAAAUCAAUUUCAAGAUUUAUGUACAUAAGAUUUUUAAAGGAAAUAGGUAAGAUAUAUAGAACUGCUUUCUAGUGUAUAUUAAGGCUAUCUCAUGCCUGCUUCUUACAUUUUUUUCUGAAGCUUAUUUCAGAAUUAAUACCGUGCCCUUCCCUGACUAAAAAAAGUUAAUCCAAGGAUUGAUCGUUGCGAAUGUAUCCCUUUUCCAAGACCUACUGCAUAGGAAGUAAGUGAGGCAGAGAUGAGAUUAUGCGGCGGAUACUUCUGAAGGAAGCGUUCUUUUUGUGUCACUUAAUCUGUGUUCACGUAACUUAGGCACUUUGGAUUUUUUAGAAUGAAAUUUCAAAAGCGCCUACACGCACCACCCAAUUUAAUGUCGUAUCUGUACUUGGGGCCUCUACACCUUUCCCAUAUUCUAAUGAAAAGAUCGUACGCCAAAGGCCACUGAGCUGGCAUCUUCUUCAUUGUGGAGAAAGUGGGAACCACAGAGCUUUUCGUGGGCCAGAUGCCCACAUAUUCCUAGCAGAGACAUGUUCUUUGUCAUGGUGUGGCUUGCCACAACAUGUCCUGUUUGGUGGCUGGCCCUCUCCGAACGGAUUCCCCUCCUCAGACCCCCAUGCACGGAUGAGCACAUAGCUCACCCUCACCCUCACACACUCACCCACACACUCACCCUCACACUCACCCACACACCCUCACACUCACCCUCCCUACACAGGCAUCGGGGCAGUUCUUUAUAUGGAUGACUAACAACUAAGAAAAAAUGAAGAUUAGUAUGAAUGGCAGGAGCAACAGGCAGUCAGAAGAGAUUUUUCUAUUUAAUCUUUUAUGUGUAACACUUUACAGCAUGAAGACGUAUUCUAUCAAUAUUUGUAUCAUAAUUGACAAAUUCUCAAGUGACAUAGGGAUUUGUUCUUGAUUCACCACUAAAGAAAAUUUUUAAAGUUAAUUUUUUUUAAUUACAGAAGAAUUCUCUUUUUAUCUUCACAAUUGUUUCAUGAUCUAUUUAUACAUUGGAUGAUAUUUAUUUAAUCCAGUUUUGUAUUAGAAAUGGAUAGUGAUGCCAAAAGCCACCGUGCUGGCUUUAAAAAUAAUAAAAAUAGUUUUUGUAUUAUUUUAAAA